CGCUGGGGACCCGGGGCGCCGCGGUGCACGGUGGCGGGCGGCCCCGGGAGAUCACCGACCCCGAAGCAAUCCCUGGCGGCGCCCGGGGUCCGGAACCCCAGCGCGGCGUCUCAGCCGCGGCGGGGUGCUCGCCACUGACCCCUCAGCCCUUGGCCGGGACUGACGUUCAAGCGGACAGCUGGGCUCUGCCGGGACUGACGUUCAAGGGGCAGCCGAGCACUUCCUGAGCCCUGCCUGGCACCCGCCGAGAGACUUUUUGGCACAAGCCUGUGGAAAUCGAAUCAAGGGUUUCUGGAGUGGAGUGAUUCCAGCUGCUUUGAGCUGAAGGAAAAGUAGCCUGGCCAGUAAAGCGUCCGUGUGCUGGAGGAGUGCAGCCACCCAUCCCGGCGGGCCUUGCAGGACGACCGACACCAGGAAGGCUUUGUGCCAGGCCCAGCAGCCACCCCCAGCCGCCUUAUGCAAGUGGGUACAUGCCCUCGCCAGACGCCAGCUUUCUGAUCUGCGUCUUUAGAUUUUUUCCAUCGCCUAAGCGUUACUUCUCCACUGAUCGGUGAGUUUAGUGAUGGCCAGAGCUCACUGGAGGACAAUGGACUUGGAUAACCAAAGGUCAGGGCUUGGUCAUAACAAUGACUUUAUUACCGGGAAGGACGAGUCAAAAAAUAGGAAGGCCUGGGAACCCUCAGGCUCGCCACUCUAGGUUUUAGAGACCUGAAACAUCACAGAAGCUUCUGAGUGGUUCUGAAGAUUCAAGAGGUUUGCAGGUUGCUAUGUUAAUGUUGUUUGUCUUUGGAGUCUUACUUCAUGAAGUCUCACUGAGUGGUCAGAAUGAAGCUCCUCCUAAUACUCACAGCAUUCCAGGCGAACCUCUGUAUAACUAUGCCAGCAUCCGCUUGCCAGAGGAGCACAUUCCCUUCUUUUUGCACAACAAUAGGCAUAUUGCCACUGUCUGUAGGAAAGACUCUCUUUGUCCAUAUAAGAAACACCUAGAGAAGCUAAAGUACUGCUGGGGUUAUGAGAAAUCCUGCAAACCAGAGUUCAGGUUUGGUUACCCAGUUUGCAGCUAUGUCGACAUGGGAUGGACGGACACUCUUGAGUCAGCUGAGGACAUAUUUUGGAAACAAGCUGACUUUGGAUAUGCCAGAGAGAGGCUGGAGGAGAUGCAUGUGCUCUGUCAGCCUAAGGAAACGAGUGACUCAAGUCUGGUGUGUUCCCGUUAUCUUCAGUACUGCAGAGCAACCAAUCUCUAUCUUGAUUUAAGAAACAUCAAGAGAAAUCAUGACAGAUUUAAGGAGGACUUUUUCCAGAGUGGUGAAAUUGGAGGGCACUGUAAACUUGACAUCCGUACAUUGACGUCUGAAGGUCAGCGCAAAAGCCCUCUGCAGUCAUGGUUUGCUGAGCUACAAAGCUAUACUCAGCUCAACUUCAGACCUAUAGAAGAUGCUAAAUGUGACAUUGUCAUUGAAAAACCAACAUAUUUCAUGAAAUUAGAUGCAGGUGUUAACAUGUAUCACCACUUCUGUGAUUUCAUCAAUCUUUAUAUUACUCAGCACGUUAAUAACUCAUUCAGUACUGACGUGUACAUCGUGAUGUGGGACACCUGUCUUUCACCUCCCGCCAUGGUUCUGAGGCCUCCCCAGCCAUGUGGAACUAGUUCUUACGGAUAUGGUGACCUAUUCUCCGACACAUGGAAUGCAUUUACUGAUUAUGACGUUAUACAUUUGAAAACUUAUGAUUCCAAAAGGGUAUGUUUUAAAGAAGCUGUUUUUUCAUUACUCCCCCGCAUGAGGUAUGGGCUGUUCUAUAAUACUCCUCUGAUAUCUGGCUGUCAAAAUACUGGACUAUUCAGGGCAUUUGCCCAGCAUGUACUACACAGACUAAACAUCACACAAGAAGGACCUAAGGAUGGAAAAAUUCGAGUCACCAUUCUUGCACGGAGCACAGAAUACCGGAAAAUCCUUAACCAAAAUGAGCUUGUAAAUGCACUGAAAACAGUAUCUACAUUUGAAGUCCAGAUUGUUGAUUACAAGUAUAGAGAACUUGGGUUUUUAGAUCAACUAAGGAUCACACACAACACGGACAUAUUUAUUGGAAUGCAUGGAGCUGGUCUGACCCAUUUACUUUUCCUUCCAGACUGGGCUGCUGUAUUUGAACUGUACAACUGUGAAGAUGAACGCUGUUACUUAGACUUGGCCAGGCUGAGAGGCGUUCACUACAUCACUUGGCGACGGCAGAACAAAGUCUUUCCUCAGGAUAAGGGCCACCAUCCAACCCUGGGGGAGCACCCGAAGUUCACCAACUACUCUUUCGAUGUAGAAGAAUUUAUGUAUCUUGUCCUUCAGGCUGCAGACCACGUAUUGCAACACCCAAAGUGGCCAUUUAAGAAGAAACAUGAUGAGCUAUAAAUAUGCUGAGUCUGUUUGCAAAAAGAGAGUGUUUAAACACUCCAACACCCAGACUUAGAAUUAAAUCAGUAAAGCAAUCUGUUAUUUCCUAUCCCCGAAUUACCUUUUCUAUGCCAAAACAUACCUUCAGGAUAUUGUUAUGUGUUGUAUAGAUGUUAAGUGUUUCAUGUGGUUUUUGUGUCAUUGCUAUUUAUCAAUAGCAAUAAUUUUGCACUGAAAACUUUUUAUAGUUCAAAAAUUAAGCAUGGACUCCCCAGUAUACUUUAACUUUCUUUCUUUCUUUUUUUUUUUUUGGAGACAGAGUCUCACUGUCACCCAGGCUGGAGUGCAGUGGCAUGAUCUCAGUUUAUGCAACUUCUGCCUCCCCAGGUUCAAGCGAUUCUUUUGCCUCAGCCACCUGACUAGCUGGGAUUGCAGCCUGCACCACCACACCUGGCUAAAUUUUUGUUGUUGUCGUUGAGAUACAGUUUCACUCUGUCACCCAGGCUGGAGUGCAGUGGCAUGAUCUCAGCUCACUGCAACCUCUGCCUUCUGGAUUCAAGUGAUUCUUGUGCCUUAGCCUCCCAAGUAGCUGGGAUUACAGGCGUGCACCACCACGCCCAGUUGAUUUUUGUAUUUUUGAUAGAGACGGAGUUUCACCAUGUUGGCCAGGCUGGUCUCGAACUCUGGGUUCAAGAAAUCCUCCCACCUUGCCUCCCAAAGUGCUGGGAUUACAGGUGUGAGCCACCACGCAUGGCCCUGAACUUUCUCUUUUUAGGAAUACCAAAGUUUUCAACUUUUUCAGCUUUAGAAUUUGUAAAUAUUUUUGUAGAAUAUCAUAUGACUGUAAUUCCAGAGUGUUCCAACUUGUUUAUGAUAUAUUUGGGUAAAUUUACAACUGUUCUUUUAUUUGCCAUAAUCUGGUUAUAACACUGUUUGUGGUAGGAAAGGAAAACAUGCAAAACAUACACACACACACACACACACACACACACACGCAGAGUUGUGAUUCUCAGUACCAAGCUAUAGGACCAUGUUAUAGAUCAGCGUUUAGUCACCUCCAGGUUAUAUGCAUCGAGAACCUGAAUAAAUCAUGCCACUAUAUUAAUUUAUAUUACAUGUUUCAUAUUUAAAUCAUGUUUUCCUAAAAUGUAGCAACUACAUGUGAUAAAAGCAAAUUAGAACAUUCUGUAGGACUGUCUUGCAUACCUUCUGUCUGGUUUCCACUGAUUCCUUCUUAGCCAUGGAGAGCAUUUGUGAUUAAUUAAUUUAUAUAUGAAAUAAUGGUUUCCAUUUUAUGCGAGUAUUUGUAACUGCAUAUACCAGUGCGUGUGCGUCUACCUCUGUCAGCAUGAAAGUAUUCCAGUCUUUAAUUUCAAAAACUUCAAAUUAGCCUCAUGAAGAGAAUUUUUCCCUGUGAAAAGUAAGACCAAGAAAAAACAAACUAAAGACAUGUGACUUAUUCAAUGAAAGUGAAAAAGAAGCUCUAAAACAGUGUCAUUGAUUAAAAAGAAUAUCUGGAAUGUAGCCCCACUCUUUGAGUGGGAUUCAUUUCUUACUGCUUAUGAACUUUCAAUUUAGUAGUCAGAAACCAUGGAUUUAUUUUACUGCACAAUGUGAAGUUUACAUUUUAUUAACACUUGAGUAGUCUGAUUUAGAGACUAGUUACUUCUAUUUUUUAAAAUAAUGGAGUAACAAAUUACAGAAUAGCUAAAUAAUUUUUUAAAAAUAUUUUACAGUUGUAAAAAAUAUCCAUCAGAAAAAUGACACACAAAACAAAAUAUCUGGACCUUUACAGAAGACGUUUGCUGACCCCCACUUUAAAGGAUUGGAACAGUCUUCUAGAAUUGAGGAAUAUUUAUUAAAAUACCUGUAAAGAAAAUAGUGAAUCACUGUAGCAAUGGCUUUGAUUCAGACCUUAAAAUCACAUAAGAAGAAUUACAACAUGUUAUGGAUUUUUAAGUGGCAGGUAUUGUAACUGUUUUUUGUGUGCAAAAUACUGAGUAACCACUGGGAAAAUAUUUCAGAUGAAAGGGAUGACAAAAGCAUGUUGCGCUUUGCAUCAGCAAGGCAUUGACUUCUGAAAAAAUGAUCUGAAAAAAGUUUCACCGUUUGUCUUCUUACCUCAUUUUAAGAAGCAUGUGAAAAUGGGAUACUAUAGACUACUGAGAAUUUCAGAAAUUGAGAACAAUUUCAUAAUAAAACGGCUAUAUUUGAAGAGAGAAUACAUUUUAUAUAAACAGGAAAAUACAUUUGACACUUUAUGGAAUUUUAUGAGACUUUUUGUGGGAACAGAAGGUCUUCAAAUUGUAAAAUGUAAAGAUUGCUCUUUUUAUUAAGUCUUUAACAGGGAUGUAUUUCAUUGUAUGUUUUGGGUAUGGCUUUGGAAUAAAUCAUUUUAUAUUUUAUUUGAA